GGCAUUUCCCGAAGAGCCAGAUCGCGGCCGGCGCCAGCGCCACCGUCCGGUCCACCCGCCAGCCCGCACAGCCGCGCCGCCGCCGAGCGUUUCGUGAGCGGCGCUCCGAGGAUCAGGAAUGGGGCUUCGGGCGCUGGGCGCGCUCCGAACCCGGCGCACGUAAGAGCCUGGGAGCGCCCGAGCCGCCCGGCUGCCCGGAGCCCCAUCGCCUAGGACCGGGAGAUGCUGGAAAUGCAACCGCCUGUUCCCCGAGGAGCCGCUGCCCCCGGGACCCCCUGGCACUGUGCGCACCCUGGUCAGCAGCCCCCGGAGAAGACGGCGCCCCCAACGCCCGACCCGCGUGGCCGUGGCAGCGCCACGCGAGCCCUCUAGGCGACCGCAGGGCCACAGCAGCUCAGCCGCCGGUGCCCCCUCGGAAACCAUGACCCCCGGCGCGGGCCCAUGGAGCCAUGGCCUAUAGGGUCCUGGGCCGCGCGGGGCCACCUCAGCCGCGGAGGGCGCGCAGGCUGCUCUUCGCCUUCACGCUCUCGCUCUCCUGCACUUACCUGUGUUACAGCUUCCUGUGCUGCUGCGACGACCUGGGUCGGAGCCGCCUCCUCGGCGCGCCUCGCUGCCUCCGCGGCCCCAGCGCGGGCGGCCAGAAACUUCUCCAGAAGUCCCGCCCCUGUGAUCCCUCCGGGCCGACGCCCAGCGAGCCCAGCGCUCCCAGCGCGCCCGCCGCCGCCGUGCCCGCCCCUCGCCUCUCCGGUUCCAACCACUCCGGCUCACCCAAGCUGGGUACCAAGCGGUUGCCCCAAGCCCUCAUUGUGGGCGUGAAGAAGGGGGGCACCCGGGCCGUGCUGGAGUUUAUCCGAGUACACCCGGACGUGCGGGCCUUGGGCACGGAACCCCACUUCUUUGACAGGAACUACGGCCGCGGGCUGGAUUGGUACAGGUGCAUGUGGACACUGUCUGAGUCAGAUCCCGGGAUGGAGGAGGCAAACACAUUGAACAGCAGAGCCCAGAGUGGGUCAGCCAUGACCACAUUCGAAUGCAGGCCAGCAUUUCCUCGAUGGAAAAUCUGAAGAUCAUUAUGACACCUUUUGCCAAUGCGAAGUGCCUUUUAAGUGCAAAACAGCAAAAUUCUGAGCAUCUGGCUUUCAGAUAGUGUGCCCUCCAAUAAAUACCUAUGCCCUGAACCCAGACUCUCCUCCCUCCCCUCUCUUCCUUCCACCACUAAACAGCAUACCUCAGGCUUCCAUCCUGGAGCCCAUGUCAUUCAGGGAUGGCUGCUUUUUAUUUUUAACCUUGGCAUGUGUGAUUCUAAGCAAGCUUAGCUGUGAACCUUAGAGAGGGAAGCCAUGUCUUAUUUUUUAUUUAUUUAUUUUUUUUUAGCACAUUUGGAUUCUGCUAAAAUUCUCAGCUGAGUCUUGGUAGGUUUUAUUUAACAUCAAGCAUGCUGACAGCUCUGCUUCUCUCUUCUCUCCCCCUCUACCACCUUUCCCCACUUUAUAUUUCUAAAAGACUAUCCUAGAGGUCUGGUCGUAAUUGCCCUCUCCCCAUUGCUUGACCAGGAAGGCUGGGAGGCUCCAGUGUCAGGAAAAGGCUGUGUGGUUUGUGCUUCUUUCAGUUACAAAUCCACACCCCUAGAGUCAAGUGUUUAGCUUGUGGAUUGCCAUUUCUGUGCAGGGUAAUACUACCCCACUUAGAUGCUGUUUCCAUAACCUCCAGAACAUCUUUCUGUAUGUAAAGAACAUUUUUGUACAUUUCUUUUUAUUAUGACCAAGUCAUACACAUUAACUGCAGAAAUCAUGGGGAUUUCUGGAAUCUUUUAAAACCCAUGUUCUUACUUUCUUCCUGAAUCCCAUGAGCUAGGUACGGUGGGUGACAGGAUGUUCCGCUCUCUGUCCACUGCCUUGUCAGUUCACAGCUUGCCAUCAUAAAGCCAGGGUCCACUGGGCAGACAUAGCCAAAGAACCCUUGCACCCAUUGGAGUGGACUGUGCUUUCCAAAGGGGGAGGUGCAGAGUUGCAGGCAGUGUGGAUCUUAGUAUGAUCUGCCCACAUCAAAGCCCCUGGUGAUAACUUCCUGAUCAGGAGGCUGAAAUCCAGAUAGUGGAAAAAUCAAAAGCUUUACCCUUAACCCAAAGGAGGGGCUUCUUUCUGUGGGUAAAUGGAGAUAAAGCUGAAGGCCGAGUGAUAUAGCCAGAAAGACACCAUCAUUUGGAGAGACCAGGAGACAGAGUCUGCACCUUCUUGUCCUUAGCCUGAUCCUUCUUGGGAACCACUCCCGUUCAGGCCACUACCAGAGAGCCCAGCCUUCUGCAGUGGGUUCUCUCCAAUUUGCUGUCUUUCUGCCAUGCCAUCUCUGAUGCUUACCUCAACUAUGUGUCUGGCCUGGGUUCUCCCCCACCCACAUUUCCUCCCCGAGGUAAGAGCUGCAGGGUGGUAUCUCCUAGCUGCUUGGACAGGUGGGCAAAGCAACACCAGGCUGAUGAGGGAACCAGGACAGGGAACCACAGUCAGAAGACCAGAGGUGGUCACCUAGGUGCUGUAUGAUUUGAAGAAAGGUGAUUCUCCCAAGUCUCAGCUUCCUCAUCAUGGAAUGGGACCUGUAGUAACUAUCCUAGAAACGUGUUGUGAAGAAUAAAUGCAAAACUGUACAUGAAAUUGCCCUGGAAAAUUCUAUGAUAUAUAAAGACAAGGCAGUAAUGUUA